AUCUCAGAGAGCGCGGGGUCCGGACAGCCGCGCGCUGAGGGUCUCGGGGCGGGCGCCGCGGGACCUCUCCGGGCCAUGGGUAAGCGGCUCUGCGGCGCGGCCCGGACAGGGGCUCGGCGGCCCUGCAGGGAGGUUCAAGGUGCCGGCGCCGGGUCCCCUCCAGCCCUCGUGGCAGUCGGUGCGCUGUGUGGGGCGGAGAGGGGCCCGGGGUGGGUUUCGGGGCGCGGGCCAAGGGGAGCGAGCCCGGCCCGCGGCUUCAGCGCUCCCCGGCCGGCGCGGAAGGGGUGAGGCUGGGCGUCCGCGCGAGCUUCGAGAAAAGGAAAGACAAAAAGUUUUGGCGGCCAGGGGCUUCCCGGGCGUUUAUCUCGAAACUCUUUUCGCCGUCUCUUGCCUGAAAUAUGCCGAGCCCGGUACGGCUCUGUCGUCCCACUUCCUGCUGCGGUUUCCACCUCGAGCUGGGCUCAGCUAAUUUGUUGUGACAGCUGUCGGCAGCCGCCCCUCCGCCCCGUGACAUCCCGCAGGUUUCAGAACCGCGGCGCCGCCGGGCACAGACUCCGGGUCCAGAGCGCGCGGCCCUUUCCUCUGCGGCCGCCGUUUCCUGAAAGGGGCUGCGCGGGUGUGAAGAACUUGCUCAAUGCGCUUUGUAGGAUCCACUGUUCCUCUUUCGGCCGCGGGCUGCGCCGAUGGUCCGGGGAGCCCGGCUUCUCGCCCCCUGCCCCUUCCUUCUCUUCCCUUUUCUCUUUUCCUCUCCUGUCUCUCCGCCCACCCGCCGCAGCCCCACAGGAGAGGGGUCGCUUCCCUGGUUGCUCUCCUCUCCUGUCCCUUGUGUGUCCCCUUGUCUUCCCUCGGUCUGCAGAAGGGACGGGGUGGCGGCUGGGGAGCGUCAGGGGAAGAGGGCAAGAGCGUGGGCUACGAGCUUGCAGGCGAUGCCCGGCUUCGCGCUCGGCGGGAGCUGCGGGCCAACCCGGGCCCGCGCUCCGUCCCUCCGCGGUGUCUAGGGGUCGCCCGGGCUGGGGUCGCGUCACCCUCCGCCCAGCGCCGGCGUGGUGGGGCUUGCGCGGUGCAGGACCCCCGAGGGCCCAGGGGGUCCCAAGGCGCUGCGGGUCCAGUGUCCCUUUGUUUGCAGAGUCUUGGGCCAGUAAGGAGUGCUCCGCGGGCCCCAGGGGAGGACAACAGGUGCCUCUUGCCCCACCCGGGCUCCUCUGGUGGGAGCCCACACGCACGGUGGCGUCACUGCGCCUACAGGCAACGCUAGAGCACAGGAGGGGUGGGAGGUCGGGGCUCGAGGGCUUCACCCCGCAGCAGAGCUCAGAGCCCAAUCCAGGCCUUAGGGACCCGCCUGGGGCCUAGAACUUGGUGUGGCAGAGGUAGAAAGGGCCUCCGAUAAUCUGCUUCUACAGUUGAGAGACGUCAACUGGCACCUCUGAGCCUCUGCCCCGUAGGUGAAAUGGGAACACACGAAACCAUCUGAGGAGCUCUCACUGUCCGUCACCACCAAAUGUGGCCCAGACUCCGUGGGGAGGGACAGUCCCAUCCUGGAACUGGGGCUUUUAGGACAUCCCAGAGCCCGGUAAGAGGGACAGGGAGAAUGGGGCUUGGAAGUUGGUAGCCUCACAUUCAGUGUCCCCCGCACCUCCUUCCCUUUCUGUACCCUCUGGUGGCUCUUGUGGCCUCAGCUGCCCCCAGACCCUGUCUCUCUCGCCCUCCCCCAAGCUGAGGUACUGAGGUUGGGCUGUGGCUUGAGCUGCACCUGUGCCCUGUUAGGGAGUGGGGGUCCCAGGCCCAUCGCGUUUCUUCUCACUGCUGGCUCCAGCUCAACACUUGGCAGGCCCCCCUCCCCAAACUGCUGGAGCAAGCUCGCGUAGACUCGGCCUGGCCGCCGCUCCCGGGCUGCCGAGUGGACCGGCCGUUUCGCCGCUUCAAAGGCUGUCUUUGUUUUGCUCCAGCUCAAGCUUAGAGAAACUUAAGCCAACAACCUCAGCCGAGGGGGCGGGGCGGCGUCUGCUGGUUGUUAUUGAGGCUGCUGUUACCAUUAUUGUGGUAAUUGACGCAGUGUUCCCAGUCGGUGACUUUUCAUGAAAGGAAGUGUCACUUCCUUCCCAUCACACCCAGGGUGAGUGGGGCGGGCAGCAGAAAGAUGGGGAGGGAGAGAAGGAAAGGGGUGUGUGCCUCCAGCAGACCCUUAAACUUGAGAGCUGUGUGGCCUUGUACUAGUCACUGCCCCUCUCUGGGCAACAGGGGUCUGUAAGUCCAUUGCGCUCAUCCUGCACCCAGGAGGCUGAUGUUUCCGGAGCACCUGCUGGGCAGCGAGGUGCCUUGGGGAGGGAGCAGGACAGGCAGGCCUCUGAUCUUCUCACUGAGCCUGGCUGUGGUUUGUGGGGGAAGCCUCCUUUCUCUUCUCACUUUUUUCUGCUGAGAACAUUGGGCACAUUGAGUCUAGCACGCCCAUCUUGUAGAUGGGGAAAGGGAGAUACAGAACCAGUGACCAACUUGGUAAGAGGUGCAGCCAUGCAGUGCUGGAACCCCUUGCCCCAUCUGUCCUCUUGGCCCACUUUCAUCUGCUUCCAGCUUGAUGUCUGGCAGGGCAGGGGCCCACUGACUUCCCCGCAUCCACCCACUGCCUGGCCCCAUAGCUACCUUCUAGUCCUGGCUAAGCCCCGUGAGACAUCUUAAGUUUGUCUUCAGUGACUCUCAACCACCGCCCGACUGCCUUCACCUUCCUGCCUUUGCAUACCUGCCUUUGCUUCGCCAGGUUGGUUGGGCCCUGGCCAGAGCUGGCCCCCUACUCUCUCAGGUAACAGGUAGCAGUUUUUUAAAUGGAAUCUCAGUAGGUAUCAACAGGUCUUUCCUCCUUCCUCAAGAUUAUGGAGAUAACACCCCUUAUUCAAAGAUGGUGGGUCCUCUGGGCCCUCCCCGACCCAGGCCAGGGAAGUUGAUUCAUAGAGUGUGGGGGCCAUGCCCCUUCCCGGCCCUCCCCCUCUCCCCGCUGCUGCCCAGCUCUCUGACCAGCCCCCUCCCAUCCCUGAGCCUGGAUGCCUUAGCAGUCAACACAGACCUGCUCUUGUUAGCAGAGUGACAGGAGCGAUGUGCUGGGAAACUGCACAUCUACUUGGGGAAAGGGGACAAGUUUGCAUCCUCUGAGCACAGAUAAGGAACUUGAGGUCUCCCUGCUCCCAUUAGAAAGAAAAAAAUCUCUAGCUCUCAGGGAUCAGCGUCUCUCAGGAGUCAGACUACCCUGGUUCUGAAUCCCAGCUCUGCCAUGGAUAAGCUCUGUGGCCCCAGGCAAGUUACUGAACCUCUCUGAGCCUCAGACAUUAUAUCUGUUAUAUCUGGAUGGCUGGGAAGAUUCAGCAAUGCAAUGUUGUAUGAGAUGCCUAGCCCACACCAGCCAGGGCACUGAUUUGAGUCGGUGGAGCAUGUAACUUGAGAACAAGUAGACCUAUGGGAGCAUCCUCUACUGGAGGCAGUGACAGACUAACAUCUUCAGUGCUGGAGUUUUAGGAUCUGGGAGUUGAGCUUGACUCAGACAGGAGCUAUGGAGUUGGAAAGAAAUCAGACUCAUAGCACAGGAAGAGCCUCAGGCAAUCCUCCUGCCCAGCACCCUGCCGCACCCCCUCUCUGCUUAGUAAGGGACUGGGUCACUAGGAGCCCAGGCUCAUCUUCUGGCGCAGCCACCUAGCCUGCCUCGGCCCUCUUCCCAGCAGUGAAAUGAGGAAAUCGCAGGGGGGCUUUUGUGGAGUGAACUACUGUUAUCAGGGUUUUUCUAACACCAUUUUCUAGCUGCACAAAACUCAAGGAACAAACUAGGAAUAAACCUCCCCAAGAAAGCACAGGGGCUUUUUAAGAAGGAACUUCUGAGGACUGCAGAGGGAAACCUGAAUUAUGGAGACACAUGGUCCUGAAAAGAAAGAUGCAAUACUGUAAAGCAGCCCCUGUCAAAGGGAACAGGAAGCAGUCCACGGAGGGUGACGCCCUAGACCCACCUGCAUCCCCCAAACCUGCUGGCAAGCAGAACGGAAUCCAGAACCCCAUCUCGCUGGAGGACUCCCCCGAGGCAGGCGGGGAGCGGGAGGAGGAGCAGGAGCGGGAGGAGGAGCAGGCCUUCCUGGUCAGCCUCUACAAGUUCAUGAAGGAGCGACACACGCCCAUCGAGAGGGUGCCCCAUCUCGGCUUCAAGCAGAUUAACCUGUGGAAGAUCUACAAAGCAGUGGAGAAGCUGGGGGCCUAUGAGCUGUCCAUGGCCCUAGGAGAGAGAAUCGGCUGGCCGCUGCUGGAGCCGCAGAGCAGCUGCCAAACUGCAGUCCUUCGAGUCCCUGCGAGGGCGGCCGGAGCUGCAAGGACCCCGCCGCCAGGGGGCGCCCGCCGGCCGCGCCCUCACGAGGUGCCCUUGCAGGUGACCGGGCGCCGCCUCUGGAAGAACGUGUACGACGAGCUGGGGGGCAGCCCAGGCAGCACCAGCGCGGCCACGUGCACGCGCCGCCACUACGAGAGGCUGGUCCUGCCAUACGUGCGGCACCUGAAGGGGGAGGAUGACAAGCCGCUGCCCACCUCCAAGCCCAGGAAACAGUACAAGAUGGCUAAGGAGAACAGGGGGGAUGAUGGGGCCACCGAGAGGCCGAAGAAGGCCAAGGAGGAGCGGCGCAUGGACCAGAUGAUGCCAGGAAAGACCAAAGCAGAUGCUGCUGACCCAGCACCACUUCCCAGCCAGGAGCCCCCCAGGAACAGCACAGAACAGCAGGGCCUGGCCUCUGGGUCUUCUGUGUCCUUUGUGGGUGCCAGCGGCUGUCCUGAGGCCUACAAGCGGCUCCUAUCCAGCUUCUACUGCAAGGGGACACACGGCAUCAUGUCACCACUGGCCAAAAAGAAGCUCCUGGCCCAGGUGAGCAAGGUGGAGGCCUUGCAGUGCCAGGAGGAGGGCUGCCGCCAUGGGGCAGAGCCCCAGGCGUCCCCAGCUGUUCACCUCCCAGAGAGUCCCCAGAGCCCCAAAGGGCUGACUGAGAACUCCAGGCACCGGCUGACCCCUCAGGAGGGAUUGCAGGCCCCAGGUGGCAGCCUCAGAGAGGAGGCGCAGGCAGGCCCCUGCCCGGCAGCCCCCAUCUUCAAGGGCUGCUUCUACACCCACCCCACCGAGGUGCUGAAGCCUGUCAGCCAGCACCCCAGGGACUUCUUCUCUAGACUUAAAGAUGGGGUGCUAUUGGGGCCUCCUGGCAAAGAGGGGCUGUCAGUGAAAGAGCCCCAGCUGGUGUGGGGCGGAGACGCUAACCGCCCUUCUGCGUUCCAUAAAGGUGGCUCCAGAAAGGGCAUCCUCUACCCCAAGCCCAAAGCCUGCUGGGUGUCCCCCAUGGCCAAGGUCCCAGCCGAGAGCCCCACGCUCCCGCCCACCUUCCCCAGUAGCCCAGGCCUGGGCAGCAAGCGCAGCCUGGAGGAAGAGGGUGCUGCCCACAGUGGGAAGAGACUGCGGGCCGUGUCUCCCUUUCUUAAGGAGGCGGAUGCCAAGAAGUGUGGGGCCAAACCUGCAGGGUCCGGCCUGGUCUCCUGCCUUCUGGGCCCAGCCCUGGGGCCUGUGCCCCCAGAGGCCUACAGGGGCACCAUGCUGCACUGCCCGCUGAACUUCACUGGCACCCCGGGCCCCUUGAAGGGCCAGGCUGCACUCCCCUUCAGCCCCCUGGUCAUCCCGGCCUUCCCGGCCCACUUCCUGGCCACCGCAGGCCCCUCGCCCAUGGCCGCUGGCCUGAUGCACUUCCCCCCAACGUCCUUCGACAGUGCCCUCCGCCACAGACUUUGCCCGGCCUCAUCUGCCUGGCACGCACCACCAGUCACAACCUAUGCAGCGCCCCACUUCUUCCACCUCAACACCAAGCUGUAGGCCAGCCCAUGGUGUUGUGUACACUGUGGAGUCGACAGGGGCCUACAACAGGCAGGUACUGCUGCCAGGGGGCUCUGAACUAGUGCCUGCUACCCAGGACACCCGGGCCAUGCCCCUGGCUGGGCAGCCUGGCACAAGUGAAGAAGAAGGCAGUGGGAAAACUGGGUUUAUCUCAAGGCAGCAGCCUGAGCCCAGGAGCAGAGGACCCAGUUGUUAUAAGGCGCUGGGAGAGGAUGGGCAGCUCCCACUGCCCCAGAGCGGAGCUCGAAGCACCCAGGUUGCCCACGGAAAAUCCAAUAAAAAGACACCAGUGUGAAUCCACGUA